AGUCCAGCCGCAACCUGGGAGUGGGAAGCUGGAGGCAGCCCAGACCUCCUGGAGCCCUGCAGUCCUGGGGCAGAGACAGAAUCAGGACACAGCUCGAGGUCAGGGCCAGAGGCUGGAGCUGAGGGCCUAGAGUGAGAGGGGGCAAGGCAAGGGGGGGAGAGGAAGAGAGGCAGGAUUAGAGAGAGGAGGCAGGCCAGAAAGAGGAGAGCAGGAGAGACCCAAAGAGAAACAGAAGGCAGAUAGAGAGGGAGUGAGAGGCAGGAGCUGAGACACAGAUCCUGGAGGAAGAAGACCAAAGGAAGGGGGCAGAGACAGAAAGGGAGGUGCUAGGACAAAACUCGAAAGGUGGCCCUAUCAGGGAAGCAGAGGAGAGGCCGUUCUAGGGAAGCCCAGCUCCGGCACUUUUGGCCCCAACUCCCGCAGGUCUGCUGGCUCCAGGAAAGGUGGAGGAGGGAGGGAGGAGUGGGAGAAUGUGGGCGCAGGGUGGGACAUGGGCAUGGCCAGGGGCAGCCUCACUCGGGUUCCAGGGGUGAUGGGAGAGGGCACUCAGGGCCCAGAGCUCAGCCUUGACCCUGACCCUUGCUCUCCCCAAUCCACUCCGGGGCUCAUGAAGGGGAACAAGCUGGAGGAGCAGGACCCUAGACCUCUGCAGCCCAUACCAGGUCUCAUGGAGGGGAACAAGCUGGAGGAGCAGGACUCUAGCCCUCCACAGUCCACUCCAGGGCUCAUGAAGGGGAACAAGCGUGAGGAGCAGGGGCUGGGCCCCGAACCUGCGGCGCCCCAGCAGCCCACGGCGGAGGAGGAGGCCCUGAUCGAGUUCCACCGCUCCUACCGAGAGCUCUUCGAGUUCUUCUGCAACAACACCACCAUCCACGGCGCCAUCCGCCUGGUGUGCUCCCAGCACAACCGCAUGAAGACGGCCUUCUGGGCAGUGCUGUGGCUCUGCACCUUUGGCAUGAUGUACUGGCAAUUCGGCCUGCUUUUCGGAGAGUACUUCAGCUACCCCGUCAGCCUCAACAUCAACCUCAACUCGGACAAGCUCGUCUUCCCCGCAGUGACCAUCUGCACCCUCAAUCCCUACAGGUACCCGGAAAUUAAAGAGGAGCUGGAGGAGCUGGACCGCAUCACAGAGCAGACGCUCUUUGACCUGUACAAAUACAGCUCCUUCACCACUCUCGUGGCCGGCUCCCGCAGCCGUCGCGACCUGCGGGGGACUCUGCCGCACCCCUUGCAGCGCCUGAGGGUCCCGCCCCCGCCUCACGGGGCCCGUCGAGCCCGUAGCGUGGCCUCCAGCUUGCGGGACAACAACCCCCAGGUGGACUGGAAGGACUGGAAGAUCGGCUUCCAGCUGUGCAACCAGAACAAAUCGGACUGCUUCUACCAGACAUACUCAUCAGGGGUGGAUGCGGUGAGGGAGUGGUACCGCUUCCACUACAUCAACAUCCUGUCGAGGCUGCCAGAGACUCUGCCAUCCCUGGAGGAGGACACGCUGGGCAACUUCAUCUUCGCCUGCCGCUUCAACCAGGUCUCCUGCAACCAGGCGAAUUACUCUCACUUCCACCACCCGAUGUAUGGAAACUGCUAUACUUUCAAUGACAAGAACAACUCCAACCUCUGGAUGUCUUCCAUGCCUGGAAUCAACAACGGUCUGUCCCUGAUGCUGCGCGCAGAGCAGAAUGACUUCAUUCCCCUGCUGUCCACAGUGACUGGGGCCCGGGUAAUGGUGCACGGGCAGGAUGAACCUGCCUUUAUGGAUGAUGGUGGCUUUAACUUGCGGCCUGGCGUGGAGACCUCCAUCAGCAUGAGGAAGGAAACCCUGGACAGACUUGGGGGCGAUUAUGGCGACUGCACCAAGAAUGGCAGUGAUGUUCCUGUUGAGAACCUUUACCCUUCAAAGUACACACAGCAGGUGUGUAUUCACUCCUGCUUCCAGGAGAGCAUGAUCAAGGAGUGUGGCUGUGCCUACAUCUUCUAUCCGCGGCCCCAGAACGUGGAGUACUGUGACUACAGAAAGCACAGUUCCUGGGGGUACUGCUACUAUAAGCUCCAGGUUGACUUCUCCUCAGACCACCUGGGCUGUUUCACCAAGUGCCGGAAGCCAUGCAGCGUGACCAGCUACCAGCUCUCUGCUGGUUACUCACGAUGGCCCUCGGUGACAUCCCAGGAAUGGGUCUUCCAGAUGCUAUCGCGACAGAACAAUUACACCGUCAACAACAAGAGAAAUGGAGUGGCCAAAGUCAACAUCUUCUUCAAGGAGCUGAACUACAAAACCAAUUCUGAGUCUCCCUCUGUCACGAUGGUCACCCUCCUGUCCAACCUGGGCAGCCAGUGGAGCCUGUGGUUCGGCUCCUCGGUGUUGUCUGUGGUGGAGAUGGCUGAGCUCGUCUUUGACCUGCUGGUCAUCAUGUUCCUCAUGCUGCUCCGAAGGUUCCGAAGCCGAUACUGGUCUCCAGGCCGAGGGGGCAGGGGUGCUCAGGAGGUAGCCUCCACCCUGGCAUCCUCCCCUCCUUCCCACUUCUGCCCCCACCCCAUGUCUCUGUCCUUGUCCCAGCCAGGCCCUGCUCCCUCUCCAGCCUUGACAGCCCCUCCCCCUGCCUAUGCCACCCUGGGCCCCCGCCCAUCUCCAGGGGGCUCUGCAGGGGCCAGUUCCUCCACCUGUCCUCUGGGGGGGCCCUGAGAGGGAAGGAGAGGUUUCUCACACCAAGGCAGAUGCUCCUCUGGUGGGAGGGUGCUGGCCCUGGCAAGAUUGAAGGAUGUGCAGGGCUUCCUCUCAGAGCCGCCCAAACUGCCGUUGAUGUGUGGAGGGGAAGCAAGAUGGGUAAGGGCUCAGGAAGUUGCUCCAAGAACAGUAGCUGAUGAAGCUGCCCAGAAGUGCCUUGGCUCCAGCCCUGUACCCCUUGGUACUGCCUCUGAACACUCUGGUUUCCCCACCCAACUGCGGCUAAGUCUCUUUUUCCCUUGGAUCAGCCAAGCGAAACUUGGAGCUUUGACAAGGAACUUUCCUAAGAAACCGCUGAUAACCAGGACAAAACACAACCAAGGGUACACGCAGGCAUGCACGGGUUUCCUGCCCAGCGACGGCUUAAGCCAGCCCCCGACUGGCCUGGCCACACUGCUCUCCAGUAGCACAGAUGUCUGCUCCUCCUCUUGAACUUGGGUGGGAAACCCCACCCAAAAGCCCCCUUUGUUACUUAGGCAAUUCCCCUUCCCUGACUCCCGAGGGCUAGGGCUAGAGCAGACCCGGGUAAGUAAAGGCAGACCCAGGGCUCCUCUAGCCUCAUACCCGUGCCCUCACAGAGCCAUGCCCCGGCACCUCUGCCCUGUGUCUUUCAUACCUCUACAUGUCUGCUUGAGAUAUUUCCUCAGCCUGAAAGUUUCCCCAACCAUCUGCCAGAGAACUCCUAUGCAUCCCUUAGAACCCUGCUCAGACACCAUUACUUUUGUGAACGCUUCUGCCACAUCUUGUCUUCCCCAAAAUUGAUCACUCCGCCUUCUCCUGGGCUCCCGUAGCACACUAUAACAUCUGCUGGAGUGUUGCUGUUGCACCAUACUUUCUUGUACAUUUGUGUCUCCCUUCCCAACUAGACUGUAAGUGCCUUGCGGUCAGGGACUGAAUCUUGCCCGUUUAUGUAUGCUCCAUGUCUAGCCCAUCAUCCUGCUUGGAGCAAGUAGGCAGGAGCUCAAUAAAUGUUUGUUGCAUGAA